ACUUCCGCUGGCCGCUGGCUCGCUGGCCGCUCCUGGAGGCGGCGGCGGGAGCGCAGGGGGCGCGCGGCCCGGGGACUCGCAUUCCCCGGUUCCCCCUCCACCCCACGCGGCCUGGACCAUGGACGCCAGAUGGUGGGCAGUGGUGGUGCUGGCUGCGUUCCCCUCCCUAGGGGCAGGUGGGGAGACUCCCGAAGCCCCUCCGGAGUCAUGGACCCAGCUAUGGUUCUUCCGAUUUGUGGUGAAUGCUGCUGGCUAUGCCAGCUUUAUGGUACCUGGCUACCUCCUGGUGCAGUACUUCAGGCGGAAGAACUACCUGGAGACCGGUAGGGGCCUCUGCUUUCCCCUGGUGAAAGCUUGUGUGUUUGGCAAUGAGCCCAAGGCCUCUGAUGAGGUUCCCCUGGCGCCCCGAACAGAGGCGGCAGAGACCACCCCGAUGUGGCAGGCCCUGAAGCUGCUCUUCUGUGCCACAGGGCUCCAGGUGGGUGUCUUAUCUGACUUGGGGUGUGCUGCAGGAAAGAGUGAUGACCCGCAGCUAUGGGGCCACAGCCACAUCACCGGGUGAGCGCUUUACGGACUCGCAGUUCCUGGUGCUAAUGAACCGAGUGCUGGCACUGAUUGUGGCUGGCCUCUCCUGUGUUCUCUGCAAGCAGCCCCGGCAUGGGGCACCCAUGUACCGGUACUCCUUUGCCAGCCUGUCCAAUGUGCUUAGCAGCUGGUGCCAAUACGAAGCUCUUAAGUUCGUCAGCUUCCCCACCCAGGUGCUGGCCAAGGCCUCUAAGGUGAUCCCUGUCAUGCUGAUGGGAAAGCUUGUGUCUCGGCGCAGCUACGAACACUGGGAGUACCUGACAGCCACCCUCAUCUCCAUUGGGGUCAGCAUGUUUCUGCUAUCCAGCGGACCAGAGCCCCGCAGCUCCCCAGCCACCACACUCUCAGGCCUCAUCUUACUGGCAGGUUAUAUUGCUUUUGACAGCUUCACCUCAAACUGGCAGGAUGCCCUGUUUGCCUAUAAGAUGUCAUCGGUGCAGAUGAUGUUUGGGGUCAAUUUCUUCUCCUGCCUCUUCACAGUGGGCUCACUGCUAGAACAGGGGGCCCUACUGGAGGGAACCCGCUUCAUGGGGCGACACAGUGAGUUUGCUGCCCAUGCCCUGCUACUCUCCAUCUGCUCCGCAUGUGGCCAGCUCUUCAUCUUUUACACCAUUGGGCAGUUUGGGGCUGCCGUCUUCACCAUCAUCAUGACCCUCCGCCAGGCCUUUGCCAUCCUUCUUUCCUGCCUUCUCUAUGGCCACACUGUCACUGUGGUGGGAGGGCUGGGGGUGGCUGUGGUCUUUGCUGCCCUCCUGCUCAGAGUCUACGCGCGGGGCCGUCUAAAGCAACGGGGAAAGAAGGCUGUGCCUGUUGAGUCUCCUGUGCAGAAGGUUUGAGGGUGGAAAGGGCCUGAGGGGUGAAGUGAAAUAGGACCCUCCCACCAUCCCCUUCUGCUGUAACCUCUGAGGGAGCUGGCUGAAAGGGCAAAAUGCAGGUGUUUUCUCAGUAUCACAGACCAGCUCUGCAGCAGGGGAUUGGGGAGCCCAGGAGGCAGCCUUCCCUUUUGCCUUAAGUCACCCAUCUUCCAGUAAGCAGUUUAUUCUGAGCCCCGGGGGUAGACAGUCCUCAGUGAGGGGUUUUGGGGAGUUUGGGGUCAAGAGAGCAUAGGUAGGUUCCAGUUACUCUUCCCACAAGUUCCCUUAAGUCUUGCCCUAGCUGUGCUCUGCCACCUUCCAGACUCACUCCCCUCUGCAAAUACCUGCAUUUCUUACCCUGGUGAGAAAAGCACAAGCGGUGUAGGCUCCAAUGCUGCUUUCCCAGGAGGGUGAAGAUGGUGCUGUGCUGAGGAAAGGGGAUGCAGAGCCCUGCCCAGCACCACCACCUCCUAUGCUCCUGGAUCCCUAGGCUCUGUUCCAUGAGCCUGUUGCAGGUUUUGGUACUUUAGAAAUGUAACUUUUUGCUCUUAUAAUUUUAUUUUAUUAAAUUAAAUUACUGCAGUGGA